CCAACGCGCAGGCGCCGCUGCUAUGCUGAGUGCCGCGUCUCGCGUAGUCUCCCGCGCCGCCGUCCACUGCGCGCUUCGCUCUCCGCCGCCCGAGGCCCGCGCGCUCGCCAUGUCCCGGCCACCGCCACCGCGGGUCGCCUCGGUGCUGGGCACCAUGGAGAUGGGGCGCCGCAUGGACGCGCCCGCCAGCGCCGCGGCCGUGCGCGCCUUUCUGGAGCGCGGCCACACCGAACUGGACACGGCCUUCAUGUACAGCGACGGCCAGUCCGAGACCAUCCUGGGCGGCCUGGGGCUCGGGCUGGGCGGUGGCGACUGCAGAGUGAAAAUUGCCACCAAGGCCAACCCUUGGGAUGGAAAAUCACUAAAGCCUGACAGUGUCCGGUCCCAGCUGGAGACGUCAUUGAAGAGGCUGCAGUGUCCCCAAGUGGACCUCUUCUACCUACACGCACCUGACCACGGCACCCCGGUGGAAGAGACGCUGCAUGCCUGCCAGCGGCUGCACCAGGAGGGCAUGUACAACGCCACCACCCGGCAGGUGGAAACGGAGCUCUUCCCCUGCCUCAGGCACUUUGGACUGAGGUUCUAUGCCUACAACCCUCUGGCUGGGGGCCUGCUGACUGGCAAGUACAAGUAUGAGGACAAGGACGGGAAACAGCCUGUGGGCCGCUUCUUUGGGAAUAGCUGGGCUGAGACCUACAGGAAUCGCUUCUGGAAGGAGCACCACUUCGAGGCCAUUGCGUUGGUGGAGAAGGCCCUGCAGGCCGCAUAUGGCGCCAGCGCCCCCAGUGUGACCUCGGCUGCCCUCCGGUGGAUGUACCACCACUCACAGCUGCAGGGUGCCCACGGGGACGCGGUCAUCCUGGGCAUGUCCAGCCUGGAGCAGCUGGAGCAGAACUUGGCAGCAACAGAGGAAGGGCCCCUGGAGCCGGCUGUCGUGGAUGCCUUUAAUCAAGCCUGGCAUUUGGUUGCUCACGAAUGUCCCAACUACUUCCGCUAGGCCCAUCAUGGCUCAGGCUGCCCAAGGCUUUUCUGUCACCUCUUUUGUUCUCUCACACUGACCAGUCUUGGCCUUAAGCUGACUUAGAAGGGUUUUUCUGAAUUGUCUAGAUCCAUGCAUUAUUUUUCUAGCUUCCUGCCUUGCUCCCUAUUCACUUUACACUGUGAAAGGUGGGGGGUGAGUCCCACUUGAGCGCUUCCUGUUGAAUAAAGCAGGCACUUGACCUGGCUGUAGCCUAGGUCUUGAGUGAACCCCAAAAACUUGCUUUCUCUGCUGUUAACACUUUGUUUCCCAUCCUACCUGGGGACUGAGAAAGGGCAGAACCAUGGGCUGGAGUCUUCAGAGGGCAGAGGUAGUAGGAGGGUCACAGAAGCACACUGCCCUCCCAGGGUCUCCUCGGGCCCCUGGUCUGAAUACCCACCUGACCUCUCAACAUUGAGGUGUCUCUCACUCUUCUACACACGAUAGAAAAGAGAGUCAUACACCUGCAGUACAUUUUCUCUAAUUCAGAGUUGCCUCAAUACAUUCUUAGGAAUGAAACAACUGGGACAAAGAAACUACCAUUAGAGUCACUACCAAGAAGAAGAACACUUCCCAGGAUCUGUGGAACAUCUUGAAGCUCUCAAUCUUAGCCUCCUCUUGUCUUAACUAAAGCCUCUUGUCUUUUCACCCAUUAGGUUCUCAGUCUUGGCUCUGGGCCUCCUGUUCGGCAUGGGGACAGACAUAGGCAGCCAAGGUCCUCAUUUCCCUUGGAAACCCCUACUCCAAACAGGAGGCACCAAGGCUGAGAAUAAGAAUCCUUGGUUCAGUGGUUGCUGAACCUGCUGCAUUCCCAGUGCACCAAAAUCCCUCCAGCCAUGGGCAGGGCAGCAGGCAGCACUUGGAGCAGCUUCUUGAAGCAAUGAAAGAGGCCCAACCUGGAAAUUUACUUUUUCAUUUAUAUUUAUUAUUUGUUCUUGAGACAGGCUCUUGCUCUGUCACCUAGACCGGAGUACAGUGGCAUGAUCACUGCUCACAGCAAUUUUGACCUCCGGGGCUCAAGGGAUCCUCCCACCUCAGCCUCCCGAGAAGUUUUUAUUUUUAUUUUUUUUGUGGAGUGGAGAUCUCCCUAUGUUGUCACCGUCUUUUCUGUUUACCCGUAACAAAACAGAUGCUCACCCAUGUGGAAUGGUGUAUCAGUUAUCUUUGCACAACAAACCACACUAAUAAGUUGCUUGAAAAGAUAAAAUCCAAGGCUGGCACAGUGGCUCAUGGCUAUAAUCCCAGCACGUUGAGAGCCCAAAGCAGGCAGAUCACUUGAGCUCAGGAGUUUGAGACCAGCCUGGGCAACAUGGUGAAACCCUGUCUCUACCAAAAAUACAAAAAAUUAAUCUGUGUGUGGUGGCACAUACCUGUGGUCCCAGCUACUCUGGAGGCUGAGGUGGGAGGAUCGCCUGGGCCCCGGAAACAGAGGUUGCAGUGGGCCGAGAUCAUGCCAUUACACUCUAGCCUGGGUGACACAGUCAGACCCCAUCUCA